AUUCAUACUGGGGAAAAACCCUAUGAGUGUAAUGAAUGUGGGAAAACGUUUGCUGAUAAUUCAGCCCUCAGGGCACAUCACAGAAUUCACACAGGGGAGAAACCCUAUGAAUGUAAUGACUGUGGGAAGACUUUCUCCAAGACAUCACAUCUCAGAGCACAUCUUAGAACUCGCUCAGGGGAGAAGCCCUAUGAAUGCAGUGAAUGUGGGAAAACCUUCUCUGAGAAGUCAUAUGUUAGUGCACAUCAGAGAGUUCAUACGGGGGAGAAACCCUAUGAAUGUAAUGUAUGUGGGAAGCCAUUUGCCCAUAAUUCAACCCUCAGAGUACAUCAAAGAAUUCACACAGGGGAGAAAUCCUAUGAAUGUAAUGAUUGUGGGAAAACGUUCUCCCAGAAAUCACACCUUAGUGCACACCAGAGAAUUCACACAGGGGAGAAACCCUAUGAGUGUAAUGAAUGCGGGAAAGCUUUUGCCCAAAAUUCAACUCUCAGAGUACACCAGAGAAUUCACACAGGGGAGAAACCCUAUGAAUGUGAUGAAUGUGGGAAAACUUUUGUCCGUAAGGCAGCUCUUAGGGUACAUCACACCAGAAUGCAUACCAGAGAGAAAACCCUAGCAUGUAAUGGAUUUGGGAAGUCCUGAGGGAAUGCAUACCUUACCACAUAACACGUAGUGCAGAAACUCAUGUGACAUAGGCUGGGAACUUGUUUCCCUUAUCCAUUUCCUUUUUCAUUAGGCUCAUAGUUUGUGGAAAAAUCCCAAUAUGCCGUUUAUUCAGGUGGGGCUGACCAUGGGAUAUGGUGCUAAUGAUAUAUAUUACAUUUACUCUUGGCCCUUAAAAAAAAAAAAGAAAAACCCUCACAGUCUUCCUGGUUCAUAAUAUGGAUUUGGAGGUUAUUUCUGCAGCAAACUUGGGUCCUGUGUGUUCAAAACCAUAAAGCACAAGGUCAAGGAAGCUAGAGUCUGAAAAACGAACAAUUCACUUCCAGGUCUUCAUCAGGGUUUUGUUUUUGUUGCUUUAAAGCAAGAGUUAAGUUUAUAGUCUGUUAAGCUCUUACAAAUUUGGCUUAUUAGUUAAAUGGACGUAGUUUAGCUUAAACUUUAUGUUAGAGUGAGAUGAAACCCUAUGAAUAUAAUCAGUUUUAGAAAAACUAAUCAGUUUAUUGUGCAUCAGAGACGUCACAUGAAGAAGAAAACUUGUUGACAUCCAGGAUGAUCAGGAGCCUUCAUUAAAACAGAAAUUUUAGGGAAAACCACAAAAACCUUCGUAAAGUGAAUUGCAUUAAACAUCAAUUAUAAUAAAAUUUCAUAUUUUGAAUAAAUGACAUUUUUCCUAGGUAUUUUUUUCUGAGGAAAUAUGUCAGUUUUAGAAUUGGAGAUAAAAUAUUCACCUAGAACUGAUGUACCAAGCUUCUGUUUUGUAAUAUCAAAAAUUUUAUAGAACAUAUAUAAGAAAAUAUUUACCUAUAGAAAAACUCACUGUAGAAUGUGAAGUUAAAAAUGGAAUAAUUUGAAUUCUGUGGAGAAUAUGAAUAAAUGUGAAUAGUUUGA